AGGCUAUUGCCGCUUCCUGUUUGGACUAGGAGCCCCGCGGUCGCAAAUUGCGAGAAUUUGGGAAGGGAAUCUUUAUCUUCUCGUCUAGUUCUCCGAGGUUGAAGGCUCGGCCUGCUCAGAGAAGGAAACUGAGGUCCACCGAGUUGGAGAAACCUACUCAACACCAGAGUUUCCUGAAUAAGUUUUUCCCAAGUUCUGUGUUAUUCUUUUUGAUGAAAGGAUACUGGCUUCCCUACAAUCAUCUUUUCAACUUCUAAAAUGUUUAAUUUUUUAAAUUGAGGCUGGACUGCAGUGGUGUGAUCAUAGCUCACUGAGACCUCAAACCCUCUUGCUCCAACUGUCUUCCCACCUCAGCCUCCUGAGUAGCUGGGACUGUAGUAGGACUAAGCUAAUGAGAGCUUUGACUUGCUUAAACGUUGGGCAGGAAAGCAGAAGAGAAAAGGGAAGUGGAAAUCAAAACAACAGAGAAAAGAAAAUGCACAUAUUUGGGAAAUAGAACAUGUUACUAACAUCUGUGUCACAUAAUAAUCAGUGGACUAACUUCUUCAGUGCUUAGAGUGUGAGAAAAAUGGCAAAUAUGAAUAGUGAUUCUAGGCAUCUUGGCACCUCUGAGGUAGAUCAUGAAAGAGAUCCUGGACCUAUGAAUAUCCAGUUUGAGCCAUCGGAUCUAAGAUCCAAAAGGCCUUUCUGUAUAGAGCCCACAAACAUCGUGAAUGUGAAUCAUGUCAUUCAGAGGGUUAGUGACCAUGCCUCUGCCAUGAACAAGAGAAUUCAUUACUACAGCCGGCUCACCACUCCUGCAGACAAGGCACUGAUUGCCCCAGACCAUGUAGUUCCAGCUCCAGAAGAGUGCUAUGUGUAUAGUCCAUUGGGCUCUGCUUAUAAACUUCAAAGUUACACUGAAGGAUACGGUAAAAACACCAGUUUAGUAACCAUUUUUAUGAUUUGGAAUACCAUGAUGGGAACAUCUAUACUAAGCAUUCCUUGGGGCAUAAAACAGGCUGGAUUUACUACUGGAAUGUGUGUCAUCAUACUGAUGGGCCUUUUAACACUUUAUUGCUGCUACAGAGUAGUGAAAUCACGGACUAUGAUGUUUUCGUUGGAUACCACUAGCUGGGAAUAUCCAGAUGUCUGCAGACAUUAUUUCGGCUCCUUUGGGCAGUGGUCGAGUCUCCUUUUCUCCUUGGUGUCUCUCAUUGGAGCAAUGAUAGUUUAUUGGGUGCUUAUGUCAAAUUUUCUUUUUAAUACUGGAAAGUUUAUUUUUAAUUUUAUUCAUCACAUUAAUGACACAGACACUAUACUGAGUACCAAUAAUAGCAACCCUGUGAUUUGUCCAAGUGCCGGGAGUGGAGGCCAUCCUGACAACAGCUCUAUGAUUUUCUAUGCCAAUGACACAGGAGCCCAACAGUUUGAAAAGUGGUGGGAUAAGUCCAGGACAGUCCCCUUUUAUCUUGUAGGGCUCCUCCUCCCACUGCUCAAUUUCAAGUCUCCUUCAUUUUUUUCAAAAUUUAAUAUCCUAGGCACAGUGUCUGUCCUUUAUUUGAUUUUCCUUGUCACCUUUAAGGCUGUUCGCUUGGGAUUUCAUUUGGAAUUUCAUUGGUUUAUACCAACAGAAUUUUUUGUACCAGAGAUAAGAUUUCAGUUUCCACAGCUGACUGGAGUGCUUACCCUUGCUUUUUUUAUUCAUAAUUGUAUCAUCACACUCUUGAAGAACAACAAGAAACAAGAAAACAAUGUGAGGGACUUGUGCAUUGCUUAUAUGCUGGUGACAUUAACUUAUCUCUAUAUUGGAGUCCUGGUUUUUGCUUCAUUUCCUUCACCACCAUUAUCCAAAGAUUGUAUUGAGCAGAAUUUUUUAGACAACUUCCCUAGCAGUGACACCCUGUCCUUCAUUGCAAGGAUAUUCCUGCUGUUCCAGAUGAUGACUGUAUACCCACUCUUAGGCUACCUGGCUCGUGUCCAGCUUUUGGGCCAUAUCUUCGGUGACAUUUAUCCUAGCAUUUUCCAUGUGCUGAUUCUUAAUCUAAUUAUUGUGGGAGCUGGAGUGAUCAUGGCCUGUUUCUACCCAAACAUAGGAGGGAUCAUAAGAUAUUCAGGAGCAGCAUGUGGACUGGCCUUUGUAUUCAUAUACCCAUCUCUCAUCUAUAUAAUUUCCCUCCACCAAGAAGAGCGUCUGACAUGGCCUAAAUUAAUCUUCCACGUUUUCAUCAUCAUUUUGGGCGUGGCUAACCUGAUUGUUCAGUUUUUUAUGUGAAAUACCUCAACUGUUUUUUUCAAGAGCUCUCAUGAUAUUUUGAGCCUUGACAACAGUUCUAUAUAAAUUCACUUGUAAAUGCUGCUGUUGUGUAAUUCUAAAUAUUUUCUAAGAUAAUUUGAAAGCAAGGGAAAUAGUGGCCCCUUAAUGAGUAUUUUUUUAUUGGGGUGGGGAAAGGGGCAAAAAGAAUGAUCUUAGUGUCUUUACCUUUCUCAUAUUAACUCACCUCUUUAUUCUGUGGUCUUUUCUGAAUAGAAAUGUAUGCCCUAGGAAGAAAUCAUGCUGGGUUUUGCUUUUAGAGAUAAAAGGUGGUGGAUUUAUUUUGCCUGCAGUAAAGAUUCUCAGGGUGUCAGAGCAGCAUAUUGUCAAAUCCUGCUUCUGUUUUAUGUUUCAGUGUAUUCACUUUCAUUUUCUUACUUACUAGACCAUUUCUGCAGUUUGCCCAAACCUCUACUGUUUGGGACAGUAAGCCAAAUACCUCAUUUUUAAAAAGAAGUUUUCAUGGCAUCAGUGUUAAUAAAGUACAUUUUUAACUGAGUCUUAAUCUCUAUUUGAAGAAAAAGUAGAGACAAAAGUAAUGUCAAUGUAAUCCCCAGGAUCAUGAAAUGUAUACAAAAUAAAUAAAGUAGGAGAGUUUGUUGCUGUCUAA